AAUAGUAUGCCAUCAUUAAACAGUUUUUGACCUUACGCAGAAACUUUAAAUGUGACAGCAGAAAGAAGCAGCAGAAAUUUACAGUGAGAAAUGGAAGACCUCUGUAGGUAAAUAAGUAAAAUGAAAGAAGCCAGAGGUGUUUUUUGUUGGCAGUAGAUGAAAUUAUUUUCAAACACUGCCCUGGGAAAAGGUGAGCCCUCAGCAACCAAGUUUAUUGACUGUCUAUUCAGGAAAUUGUAUUAGUUGCUUUGGAAAGAGAAAGGAAAAAGAAAAGACUUUCUGCCAACUGAGGGCUGGAAAACUUGAGGGAGAUAAAGUAUUUACAUGCUUUAAUAACAUAAAGCAUGUCCAAAAGAAAUACAUAAUUACAGCUAUGUUUGGCACUGAAAAUAAUCCAGGUUAUUAUAUUUUUAAAAUUGUGUGUGAAUAUGUAAGUGAAUGCCCUUGAGUCAGAAAUGCUUGAGUGAUAAUAUUUCUUGAGAGAAUGGAAAAGUAGAUGGUAUUAGGAGCUAAAAAGAGAGAGAAGGGAUAAAGGAUGACCACUAGUUAAGAAGGAACAGUGAACUUUUUUUCUUUAGAGGGGACAUAUUUCAUAUGCAUAGUUAUUCCCCCUCUACUUCUAAUCUUAGUAUAAUAAGCAUUUAACUUCCCAUAGGACCUUAGCAGUCUGCAUGUUAUUACUAAAAGCCCACAGGUAAGGGAAAAUUAGACCCCUAAAUUAAAGACCUGACCAUCUUGCUCCUGAAGUUUUAGGUUUUCCAACUUUAUUUCCAGUGUAUCUUGGACAAAGACCCUUUGAGAGCUCAGAAAAUUAGGAGAUGUGGUCAACACAUUCUUCUUAAUAUCUAGUGCAACCAAAGACUUGGCCAGCAACUAAGGCCAGCAACUGGAAAAUGGGUGUGGUGUCAGGUUUCAGACGCCCCCAUAGUUGUCUUCACGUCCUUUAAUAUGUGUUGGCAUCCCUCAAGCCCUGCCAGUUUAUGCUCUUUCCUUUGUGAAGCCUUCCUGCCCUGCCCAGGAAAAAGUAAUGCCAUCCCCCAUCCCCCAUCCCCCAGUGACCAUAAAUAGCACUUUCUCCUUCCCCUGUUAUAGCACUUUUCAUACUGUGUUAGAGUUCACAUUUCUGUCUCUCUGCCUCAUUGUGAUCUAUUUGAGUGCCAGGAUUGUGUGUUAUUCUAGCGCUUGGCACACAGGAAGAACUCAAUGAGCAUUUGUUGACUAAAUCUAGACUCAAGGUCAUCCAAGAUAUUAUACAAAAACUUUUUCAUCGAACCAUUUGGUCUGCAUUGUGGAAACUGAAACGAAUGGCACUCCCCGUUAAGAGAAUCCCAGUGAGAAGCCAUAGCAUUGCAGGAGGAAGCUCAAACUGGUUAACUUUGCUCAUGCCGAUCAGUCUUAGAAUUUUUUGUAAUGUUUCCAUGAUGAAUUAGUUUCAGCUGUAUUUUUUUGGCAAAUAUUUAAAGAUAAUUUUUAUUUGUGUGGACUUUUCUUCUUGUCAGUUUGUCAUAAAGGUGUCAUCUUUCAUUCACUAACCCCUUAUCAGCUUAUAGGAAUUUUCCUCGUGGGUGGUUGCUUGUAACCUUCUCUUGACUGCCAGGGAUCUGAUAUACUAAACGGUUGAGAUACUGUGGUGAUCAGCUGCUUGUAAACAAUAACUGAUAAAUCGGUUAUAAAUUAUCAACACACUUCAGAUGACCAUAUCAUCAUGACUUGGUGAUAGCAAAAUAGACUUCUGAAUUCUCAGCUAAUCCAGGAUUGUGUCUUAACAAACAUUUAUGUUGAUUAAUCAGGAGGGUGUUUAGUUUAAGAAACAUGUACUGAAUGUUCAAUAUGUGAGUGCCAAGUGCAGUGUGGUGCAACCUGUUUACUGCUUCAGGUGAUCUCCAGAUAUCCUAAGGAAUUUUUAACUGUACAGCUUCUUUGGGGAAGGAAAUCCUAAGCCAACAACCUGAGGGUGGAAGUGUGUGACUGGGAAUAAUUAAAAUGCCUCACAAUGGUUCGAGCAGGAAUUCCAUAGGAAUGCACUUUAAGGCAUUUAGGAAAGCAAAAUUCCGUUUGGAUUUACUCCAAACCCUAUGACUUCAGAGACAGGAAUUUUUGAUGAUUAGUGGCUGGAGCCCCAACUUGUUAUUUAGUAAUUCCACAUUCAGUGUGGAAUUGUUUUUUCUGUAGCACUAGUUAUAAGUUCUUUGUUUGUUUUUCUAAAGGUUUUAAGGAGGUUUACAAAUUAAGAUGGAAUAAGACAUUAGAAACUUAAGGAUACAUAGCAAAUUAAAACCUUGAUACAUUUGGUGCUAAGCUUUUCAGCUGCUAAAGAUAGAGAGUUUUGGCCAAGAUAAAGUAUAUAGAGUCAAAGACACAUGCAGAAUUCUCCUGGAUAUAAGUUCAGGUACCUGUGCCAUUUUAUCACUUUAGUCAAUGUGCCCAUUUUCUUAGGGCAGGUUUAAUUUUCUGCUGCGGCAUGGCCCUUCAGCUUUCCCAAGUUUACGAUGCUCAUCUCAUACCUGAUGGAAAUUGUUGAUAAUGUUAGUGUAUGGUUGGUGGCUUUCCCAGUAGCCCACUUCAGAUCCUUUUAUUGGUCAUCACCAGUUACAAAAGUUUUAGGAAAGGGAAGGAGAGAAGCUGGAACUGAUGGCUAAGUAAAGUUAUAGCUGUAGAGCUCUGGUUGUCCAUAAUGAACAGUGGCAAUGAACAGUGAAGAUUUAAGCAAGGUUAUUUUUUGAGGGUCCACUGAUGAUUUUCCUAUAACUCGUUAAAAAUAUUUUUAAAACUUUUAUAUGGCUUCAUAUAAAAAAAGCUUAAAAAUCUGUUCCCAGACUUCCUAGGCAGGUAUGUUUUCUUUUCAGUGUUGCCUUCUCUAAGACUUUAUCAGCAGAAGGAGUAUUUGAGCUGAUGGCAAAUGCUGCCAAAAUGAGAAGUGUGUGUGUUUCUCAAAACUCAUGAUCCCACAGUUAAAUCGAGGGUGUGGGUAAAGGACCCAGAACUGUUCUUGCUGAUGGAAUAGCACACUUUUCCUCAGACAUUAGUAGAGUAAAUGAAUGGAGGCAGAGGAUUGGGAAACACUCUUGAAGGAGGGAGUGCCCAUCAGCCUGUAAGCCAAAGUAAACAGUUCUUGUAACUGAAAAAUAGACUUCCUGGAAGGAGAGAACCAGAGAAGUGGGUGUGAAGUGCAACCAGCAAGUACCAUUUUCAGUGAUACAGACAGCUGGCUUAACCUGAGUCCUGACAAGAACCUCUCAGAGCUAUUUGGGGAAAUCAGUUGCUUGAACCAGCCUUUGACUGGCCUAUCGUUCCUACAGCUGUACCCAAAGAUGGCACUUGGGGAGAAAAGGUCACAUUUGUUUGUGAUAGAGAAAGCAAACCGAUGGGGCAUUUUGAGAGGUAGAAAUGAAGUCAUCAUUUGCGGAGCCGGUGGACCAGCAGAAUGGCCGUGGGAAGGUAUCCCUGAACCUGUAUGUGUGGAAAUGCAGGCAUUCUCUGUCAGUCUUUUGUCACAGUGAGAAAAUGUCAUUACAGUGGACAGCUAUGCACACGUUGGAGAUUAUGUGAUGUGUGCAUGUGCAUCCAUGUGUACAACAUACACCCAUGCAAAAAUUGCUCACAGGGUCAUGUGCGUGUCCUGGUAGUCUGUUAUGUCCAUUCUUCUGUAAUAGGAGUAUGUUUUUCAAACUGAAGCUGUUAGGUUCUGUUAAUUCCAACAGAACAAAAAAAAAUCUGCCUCUGGCCAUCAUUCGUUAAUUUACAUAGAUUAGAUACAUGUAGUCUGUCUCCUAAGUGGCUUACAUAAAGCCGUGGGCGUCUUUUCCUGUGUCUCCUCUUCGGCAGUUCCUAAGGCACCUACCAGGUUUAUAGUUGCUGAUGUCCUACCCAUACUAUGUGUCAAGAAAGGUAGACUCAAAAAGGAUUGAUGCAGAUAUUCCUUAGAAGUUUUCAUGCCCAAAGAUUCUUGGACCUUAGUUGCAUGAGGGAAGAGGCCUUGCCUCGUGAAAGGAGACCGAAGCCCCUUAUUAAAGGGGUCACUCAGAAAAAGGUGUUAUCUAAAUUCCCUCUUUGUAGUUUUAUUUCUUCAAUGUAUUCCCCAUCACUAGCUGUGUGUGCUGGAGCCAAAUGUUGGGCCCACUGCCAUCUUUUAAAGAAUGCUACUGUAAAGGGAUAACUUUACUAGACAGUUUGGGAAAUAGAAGAAACAAUUAUCUAAAAUGCUCUUGUUCCAAACACAAAAACUAGCUUCAUGUUUUUGUGUAUAACCCUGCCUAGUCUUACUCUGUAGACAUCCUUCCCCCCACACCCAUCGUGUAUGUUUUUUAUCCCCAUCUAACAUUAUAUCAAAUACAUUGUCCUAUGUUGCUACCUUGUCUUCAUUAUUAUGAUUUGUCAAGCAAUUGGGUUGUACUGACUGCAGUGUUACUCCUCAUUUCCUUUCCCCCUUUCUUUUCCAUACUACUUAAAAAGCAAGAAAGGAAAAAAAAUUCUAUUUAAGAGAAAAUCCUAUGUAGUCGUAAUGGAAUUUAUUUUCCUGAGUGCCUGGGCGUGCUCCAAACAGAUAGCUGUGAUUGUGUCAUCUCUUCUUACUAAGCAUCUGACCACUCACUACCUGUGCAUCUGAUCCCUAGGCUCAUGGCAUGAGGGCUGUGGCUCUUGAUGUUUUUUUUUUUGAUGUGCUUAGUAUCACCAGAACUGUAUUGACUCUAAGAGUAUGGAAGCUUUGUAAAGUUAACUAACGAUUUGUAGGUUUUGUGCAAAUAGCCAGCUCUCCAGGUAGAGACAUUUUAAUUCUGUUGCUUUUUUUUUUUGUAGCAUAUUAUUAUAUUGCAGAUGUUUACUUAGUAUGAAAAAUGGAUAUAAUUAAGUUCUAAAUGGGUACUAGAUAUUAACUUCAAAAUGAAUUUGCAACUUGUAUGCUUUGCAUAUGCCGUAUGCUUUGCAUAUGCCAUAUGCUGUUGUUUCCAAGGAUGUAAAGCAGUUUUCCACUUCCACCAUCUUAUAAAUUAAAACCAGAGGGCUAGACGUUAUCCAGCAAGGGACCUACAAAAUUCGAAAAAAAACUUCGGAUCAUUAUCAGGAUUAAGUUUGUUGAAAUUGUAUCAGGAAAAUAGACUUUUCCUUGUAUUAUUAUUGACUCAUAUAAUGCAACUCAUACUGGUUUCAUAUUCAGAAGGUAUAUAGCACCUGUUGUAAUAUUUCAGGUUGAUUUCUGCAAUCUUUAUUUAAAAAUACAAAUCCGCAAAGCAAAUUGCAUAAACGGUAUACAAAAUGAAAUCACCAGGCUUCAAAUAUAUUUUAUGUAAAUGUUAAGUGCUCUUUAGAUUAGCAAAAGGAAGACAAACAUUUUGAUUACCUCUUUAAUACUAAAUUUUUGUUUCUGAAUUAUAAAUCUUUGAAGAUAUAAUUAGUGUAAGAUAUAUACCAAUCAACAUAGUCCAGAAAACCCUGAACCUGGCUGCUUAUUAGUUGGAAAGAGUACCUAUUUAGACUUUCUAAGCCACAGUAUGUGGCUAAGUGAUUAAUAUGCACUAUUACACUUUCACAAAUACUUUUUGGACCAACAUAUUGACUUAAGGGAGCAUACUUUGUACUAAAAAACUAAUUUGAAGGUGAAAUCACAGCAAAUUUAACAGUUCAACCUUGUGUAUUUGUAGAGUUUUAGUUGGAUCAUAGGAUAAUGACAUUAGCUAAAGUCAGCAAGCAUGUAAAAUAAACAUUUUGAAGUUUAAUAGUCAUUUAUGUUCUACAAUAAUAAAUAUUUGGCACCCACCAUAACCACCACUACCAAAAUAUGUAUGCUGAAAUUGUGUCUCCAGGAUGAAUAAAGAGGUGUAAGGCAAGCUGACACCCAUUAGAAAAAAAGGUUUAGAAAGGGAGAGAGGGCCUGGACUUCCCUAAGCUUAACCCCAACAUAGGGCCUGUAGCUCCUGUUGGAACCAAUUUAUAAAACUUCAAGGUGGGAAUCAAUAGAUUGUUUCCAGUGUUAUAUAGUUCCUCUUUAAUCAGUUGAUCUUCAACCAAAGCUUCAAGUGGUUUUUGUUUUUAUUUAUUGCCAAAAGCUUCUUAACCAAUGUGAUUAUAAAUGUUUAAAUUCAUUUACAGUGAAAUGGAUUUGUAUCUUCCUUGCUCUACAGUAGAUAGUGAAGCCUCCGUGACCUGUGUAAGCUGCAGGUUGAGGAGAAUGUUUAAACAGUAGGCGAGCGUUCAUACAGUGUCCCUGGACUGCAUUUCCUUGCUUACAGAGCCUUGGAGCUGGGCCAACUCGCAUGAGCGGGAGGAGGAGAGGCUCAGUUUUGAGAGCCCUGGGUUUAUUUCUGGCUGUGGGGAUACGAGAAUGUGGGAGAAGGUGUAAACAUAGUUUGAGGGAGGUCGUAGACUUGGAGGUUCUUGCCAGGGGUAAAUGCUGGCUGGAUUUGUUUAUGGAUGGAUUUGAUUAUAGCUGCUUCACGCUUUUACCUCUGGAGUUGGUGCUUCCAAGGGGUGAUGCUCAUUGUCUGGAUCUCCUUUAGUGGGCAUCUCAGAAUUCUUUGCUGCACCAACCACAGCAUUUCUUUUCCCUUUCUUUUGGUAUUUGUAUUCAAAUGCCUGACUUCCUGACCUGCUGUGAGGGUUUUUAAAAAUAAUGAACACCAAGCUUCUUGGGAAAAGACAGGUAUGUAAAUACUGCAAGCUUAUAGCAUUUGGGGGAUGGAGUUGUGGGAUUUUGGAGUUUGUGACCCCCAUGUGUCUGUGUAUCACUCUCUCUAAUGUAGAGAGACAGAGCAGCAGUUCCUGAGCUCUGUCUUUUGUCUCUUCAUGGGUUGGUCACUGAUUUCCCCUUUCAGGGUCUGAAUCCCUUUCCCUUGCCUCCCCCCAUGUGGGUUCCGGAAGGCCCACAUCCAACAGCUGCCCUUGGUCAACCCCCAGCCCUGCACACAGGUGUUUUCUGCUGUUCAGAGCUCAGGGGCGCUGUCCAGCCAGCUGAUGACAGCUCACUGGUGGCGCUGGUCUCACUCCAGUGCUGGCUCUGCCCUCUUGGCCCUGUUGCUUCCUCCUUGGAGGAUUAGUCACCCCAGUCUUGGGGCAUUUUACCCACCUGUAUGACUAGCACACAUUGCAUCCACUUGCCAAGGAGUGUUAGGGAUACAGUCUCAAGAAAACCUGCCCAGUAGAAAUGACUUCCUCUGGAGAAAUUUAGAUGAUAAAUUCCAUAGGGAGAAAUCAUGUUUUAUUAAUGAGAAACAAAAUCGUGCACUAGUGGGAGUUCAGGCUCAGAAGCCAGUGCAUAGUCCAGCCUGGCGACCUGGCAUGGUGUGUUACCCUGGCCAAAGCUCCCCAACCUCUGUUCAUGAUUUCCCUCUGUAAAAUGGGAAUAACAAUAGUAUCCAUUUCUUUUGGGUGGUUAUAAGGAAUACUUAAGUUAACUCAUUCAUGUAAAGCACUUGAAUAGUGGCUUGUAUACAGUAAGCACACAGUAAAUGUACAUUGUCAUUGUAUCUUUGUACCUCAACAUCUGAAACUAUGGUUUAUACAUAGCACAUACUCAUUCAUGCUUUGUUGAGUAAAUGUAAUAUUCAGAAGGUGGGAAAGUGAUUUCCUUCUCUCUUAUCAUAAAAUAAGAGUUAUAUUUGGUUGAAAUAAGGCAUCAUAGGCCUGAAGACAUUUACUCCCUGGCUGCUGGCAGGGGAGUAGAAUGUUCCAAACUCUAUGUUGAUAACUGGGUGCCUAUGAUUUGUUAAUCAUACCUAACAAACUCAGUCUGUCAGGUGUUUCAGUAAAAUUUACUGACUCCCAAGGUAAUUUUGAAAGGACAAAGCCAUCAGGUGAUUUGUUUUCAAUAAGCAUUAUUGGGAUAUUUCAGACUCCAACAUGUGCAGUGGAGAUAUUAACGAGACUUUACCCUUUCUAAACUUAGGGGCUUACUCUGCAUUGUAACGUAUGUUUGCUUUUAAGGCGAUAGAUGGGUAGAUAGAUGCUCUGUAAUUGAAUAGCCUACUGGGCUUCUGUGUAGCACAGCACUGUGUAAGUCGCAGGUGUUCAGUAAAUGUAUUUUAAAUCAAUGAGUAAUUGAUGGGAUAUUUUUCUUCACAUUACAUCACAUUGAAGAUGCUUGUGAGGAAGUUUUGUUCAUGAUUGUCCUCCUAGGCAGGCGCCACCUAACAUGUUUCUCUCUAGCUGCGGGGUAUUGAAUUUGAGGCUGCUCUCAGCAUUACUGCUCAUCUCAAAGAGGAACAAAUGGUCCCCCAAAUGGUCCAGAUGCAACAGUAGGGAAAGGAGUGCCACCAUUCAUUCUGAGGUGCCUGGGCCAUACUCUGGAUGAAGCUCACAGCUCUAACGUAAGGCGAUGAGAACUGGACUGAUGACCAACUGCUUGGUUUUAAACCAUGCAAUGAAAACCUUAUUGCUGGCUGCAAUAUAAUCAAUGGGAAAUGUGAAUGUAACACCAUUCGAACCUGCAGCAAUCCCUUUGAGUUUCCAAGUCAGGAUAUGUGCCUUUCAGCUUUAAAGAGAAUUGAAGAAGAGAAGCCAGAUUGCUCCAAGGCCCGCUGUGAAGUCCAGUUCUCUCCACGUUGUCCUGAAGAUUCUGUUCUGAUCGAGGGUUAUGCUCCUCCUGGGGAGUGCUGUCCCUUACCCAGCCGCUGCGUGUGCAACCCCGCAGGCUGUCUGCGCAAAGUCUGCCAGCCGGGAAACCUGAACAUACUAGUGUCAAAAGCCUCAGGGAAGCCGGGAGAGUGCUGUGACCUCUAUGAGUGCAAACCAGUUUUCGGCGUGGACUGCAGGACUGUGGAAUGCCCUCCUGUUCAGCAGACCGCGUGUCCCCCGGACAGCUAUGAAACUCAAGUCAGACUAACUGCAGAUGGUUGCUGUACUUUGCCAACAAGAUGCGAGUGUCUCUCUGGCUUAUGUGGUUUCCCCGUGUGUGAGGUGGGAUCCACUCCCCGCAUAGUCUCUCGUGGCGAUGGGACACCUGGAAAGUGCUGUGAUGUCUUUGAAUGUGUUAAUGAUACAAAGCCAGCCUGCGUAUUUAACAAUGUGGAAUAUUAUGAUGGAGACAUGUUUCGAAUGGACAACUGUCGGUUCUGUCGAUGCCAAGGGGGCGUUGCCAUCUGCUUCACCGCCCAGUGUGGUGAGAUAAACUGCGAGAGGUACUACGUGCCCGAAGGAGAGUGCUGCCCAGUGUGUGAAGAUCCAGUGUAUCCUUUUAAUAAUCCCGCUGGCUGCUAUGCCAAUGGCCUGAUCCUUGCCCACGGAGACCGGUGGCGGGAAGACGACUGCACAUUCUGCCAGUGCGUCAACGGUGAACGCCACUGCGUUGCGACCGUCUGCGGACAGACCUGCACAAACCCUGUGAAAGUGCCUGGGGAGUGUUGCCCUGUGUGCGAAGAACCAACCAUCAUCACAGUUGAUCCACCUGCAUGUGGGGAGUUAUCAAACUGCACUCUGACAGGGAAGGACUGCAUUAAUGGUUUCAAACGCGAUCACAAUGGUUGUCGGACCUGUCAGUGCAUAAACACCGAGGAACUAUGUUCAGAACGUAAACAAGGCUGCACCUUGAACUGUCCCUUCGGUUUCCUUACUGAUGCCCAAAACUGUGAGAUCUGUGAGUGCCGCCCAAGGCCCAAGAAGUGCAGACCCAUAAUCUGUGACAAGUAUUGUCCACUUGGAUUGCUGAAGAAUAAGCACGGCUGUGACAUCUGUCGCUGUAAGAAAUGUCCAGAGCUCUCAUGCAGUAAGAUCUGCCCCUUGGGUUUCCAGCAGGACAGUCACGGCUGUCUUAUCUGCAAGUGCAGAGAGGCCUCUGCUUCAGCUGGGCCACCCAUCCUGUCGGGCACUUGUCUCACCGUGGAUGGUCAUCAUCAUAAAAAUGAGGAGAGCUGGCACGAUGGGUGCCGGGAAUGCUACUGUCUCAAUGGACGGGAAAUGUGUGCCCUGAUCACCUGCCCGGUGCCUGCCUGUGGCAACCCCACCAUUCACCCUGGACAGUGCUGCCCAUCAUGUGCAGAUGACUUUGUGGUGCAGAAGCCAGAGCUCAGUACUCCCUCCAUUUGCCACGCCCCUGGAGGAGAAUACUUUGUGGAAGGAGAAACGUGGAACAUUGACUCCUGUACUCAGUGCACCUGCCACAGCGGACGGGUGCUGUGUGAGACAGAGGUGUGCCCACCGCUGCUCUGCCAGAACCCCUCACGCACCCAGGAUUCCUGCUGCCCACAGUGUACAGAUCAACCUUUUCGGCCUUCCUUGUCCCGCAAUAACAGCGUACCUAAUUACUGCAAAAAUGAUGAAGGGGAUAUAUUCCUGGCAGCUGAGUCCUGGAAGCCUGACGUUUGUACCAGCUGCAUCUGCAUUGAUAGCGUAAUUAGCUGUUUCUCUGAGUCCUGCCCUUCUGUAUCCUGUGAAAGACCUGUCUUGAGAAAAGGCCAGUGUUGUCCCUACUGCAUAGAAGACACAAUUCCAAAGAAGGUGGUGUGCCACUUCAGUGGGAAGGCCUAUGCCGACGAGGAGCGGUGGGACCUUGACAGCUGCACCCACUGCUACUGCCUGCAGGGCCAGACCCUCUGCUCGACCGUCAGCUGCCCCCCUCUGCCCUGUGUUGAGCCCAUCAACGUGGAAGGAAGUUGCUGCCCAAUGUGUCCAGAAAUGUAUGUCCCAGAACCAACCAAUAUACCCAUUGAGAAGACAAACCAUCGAGGAGAGGUUGACCUGGAGGUUCCCCUGUGGCCCACGCCUAGUGAAAAUGAUAUCGUCCAUCUCCCUAGAGAUAUGGGUCACCUCCAGGUAGAUUACAGAGAUAACAGGCUGCACCCAAGUGAAGAUUCUUCACUGGACUCCAUUGCCUCAGUUGUGGUUCCCAUAAUUAUAUGCCUCUCUAUUAUAAUAGCAUUCCUAUUCAUCAAUCAGAAGAAACAGUGGAUACCACUGCUUUGCUGGUAUCGAACACCAACUAAGCCUUCUUCCUUAAAUAAUCAGCUAGUAUCUGUGGACUGCAAGAAAGGAACCAGAGUCCAGGUGGACAGUUCCCAGAGAAUGCUAAGAAUUGCAGAACCAGAUGCAAGAUUCAGUGGCUUCUACAGCAUGCAAAAACAGAACCAUCUACAGGCAGACAAUUUCUACCAAACAGUGUGAAGAAAGGCAACUAGGAUGAGGUUUCAAAAGACGGAAGACGACUAAAUCUGCUCUAAAAAGUAAACUAGAAUUUGUGCACUUGCUUAGUGGAUUGUAUUGGAUUGUGACUUGAUGUACAGCGCUAAGACCUUACUGGGAUGGGCUCUGUCUACAGCAAUGUGCAGAACAAGCAUUCCCACUUUUCCUCAAGAUAACUGACCAAGUGUUUUCUUAGAACCAAAGUUUUUAAAGUUGCUAAGAUAUAUUUGCCUGUAAGAUAGCUGUAGAGAUAUUUGGGGUGGGGACAGUGAGUUUGGAUGGGGAAAUGGGUGGGAGGGUGGUGUUGGGAAGAAAAAUUGGUCAGCUUGGCUCGGGGAGAAACCUGGUAACAUAAAAGCAGUUCAGUGGCCCAGAGGUUAUUUUUUUCCUAUUGCUCUGAAGACUGCACUGGUUGCUGCAAAGCUCAGGCCUGAAUGAGCAGGAAACAAAAAAGGCCUUGCGACCCAGCUGCCAUAACCACCUUAGAACUACCAGACGAGCACAUCAGAACCCUUUGACAGCCAUCCCAGGUCUAAAGCCACAAGUUUCUUUUCUAUACAGUCACAACUGCAGUAGGCAGUGAGGAAGCCAGAGAAAUGCGAUAGCGGCAUUUCUCUAAAGCGGGUUAUUAAGGAUAUAUACAGUUACACUUUUUGCUGCUUUUAUUUUCUUCCAAGCCAAUCAAUCAGCCAGUUCCUAGCAGAGUCAGCACAUGAACAAGAUCUAAGUCAUUUCUUGAUGUGAGCACUGGAGCUUUUUUUUUUUUACAACGUGACAGGAAGAGGAGGGAGAGGGUGACGAACACCAGGCAUUUCCAGGGGCUAUAUUUCACUGUUUGUUGUUGCUUUGUUCUGUUAUAUUGUUGGUUGUUCAUAGUUUUUGUUGAAGCUCUAGCUUAAGAAGAAACUUUUUUUAAAAAGACUGUUUGGGGAUUCUUUUUCCUUAUUAUAUACUGAUUCUACAAAAUAGAAACUACUUCAUUUUAAUUGUAUAUUAUUCAAGCACCUUUGUUGAAGCUCAAAAAAAAUGAUGCCUCUUUAAACUUUAGCAAUUAUAGGAGUAUUUAUGUAACUAUCUUAUGCUUCAAAAAACAAAAGUAUUUGUGUGCAUGUGUAUAUAAUAUAUAUAUAUACAUAUAUAUUUAUACACAUACAAUUUAUGUUUUCCUGUUGAAUGUAUUUUUAUGAGAUUUUAACCAGAACAAAGGCAGAUAAACAGGCAUUCCAUAGCAGUGCUUUUGAUCACUUACAAAUUUUUUGAAUAACACAAAAUCUCAUUCUACCUGCAGUUUAAUUGGAAAGAUGUGUGUGUGAGAGUAUGUAUGUGUGUGUGUGUGUGUGUGUGUGUGCGCGCGCACGCACGCCUUGAGCAGUCAGCAUUGCACCUGCUAUGGAGAAGGGUAUUCCUUUAUUAAAAUCUUCCUCAUUUGGAUUUGCUUUCAGUUGGUUUUCAAUUUGCUCACUGGCCAGAGACAUUGAUGGCAGUUCUUAUCUGCAUCACUAAUCAGCUCCUGGAUUUUUUUUUUUUUUUUUUCAAACAAUGGUUUGAAACAACUACUGGAAUAUUGUCCACAAUAAGCUGGAAGUUUGUUGUAGUAUGCCUCAAAUAUAACUGACUGUAUACUAUAGUGGUAACUUUUCAAACAGCCCUUAGCACUUUUAUACUAAUUAACCCAUUUGUGCAUUGAGUUUUCUUUUAAAAAUGCUUGUUGUGAAAGACACAGAUACCCAGUAUGCUUAACGUGAAAAGAAAAUGUGUUCUGUUUUGUAAAGGAACUUUCAAGUAUUGUUGUAAAUACUUGGACAGAGGUUGCUGAACUUUAAAAAAAAUUAAUUUAUUAUUAUAAUGACCUAAUUUAUUAAUCUGAAGAUUAACCAUUUUUUUGUCUUAGAAUAUCAAAAAGAAAAAGAAAAAGGUGUUCUAGCUGUUUGCAUCAAAGGAAAAAAAGAUUUAUUAUCAAGGGGCAAUAUUUUUAUCUUUUCCAAAAUAAAUUUGUUAAUGAUACAUUACAAAAAUAGAUUGACAUCAGCCUGAUUAGUAUAAAUUUUGUUGGUAAUUAAUCCAUUCCUGGCAUAAAAAGUCUUUAUCAAAAAAAAUUGUAGAUGCUUGCUUUUUGUUUUUUCAAUCAUGGCCAUAUUAUGAAAAUACUAACAGGAUAUAGGACAAGGUGUAAAUUUUUUUAUUAUUAUUUUAAAGAUAUGAUUUAUCCUGAGUGCUGUAUCUAUUACUCUUUUACUUUGGUUCCUGUUGUGCUCUUGUAAAAGAAAAAUAUAAUUUCCUGAAGAAUAAAAUAGAUAUAUGGCACUUGGAGUGCAUCAUAGUUCUACAGUUUGUUUUUGUUUUCUUCAAAAAAGCUGUAAGAGAAUUAUCUGCAACUUGAUUCUUGGCAGGAAAUAAACAUUUUGAGUUGAAAUCA